CUCGGGAGCCGUGAGCCGGGAAGAGGGAGACGGGCAGGGCGGCGCCAGCAGGCCCUGGUGGGCUUGGGAGGAGGCAGGAGACUGGAGACAGCCUCGGCUAGAGCGGACACAGGCACCUGGCAAGCUUUCCUUGACCAAAUCAAGGUUGUCCUUGUCCUAUUAAGCCUCUUCCCCUUGCCUUGAAGGGACCUCACCUGGUGCCCUGACCUCAGCCUCCUCCCCAAACCCCGCUGGGGAGUGACCUGCUUCUAGGCCUCCAUCCACAAAGCUACGGACUUGCAGCCCACGGGACCCCAGCCCAGGGCCUGCUGCCCUCACCAUGGUGAAAUUGCUGCCGGCCCAGGAGGCAGCCAAGAUCUACCAUACCAACUAUGUGCGGAACUCGCGAGCCGUGGGCGUGAUGUGGGGUACCCUCACCAUCUGCUUCUCCGUACUGGUCAUGGCCCUCUUCAUCCAGCCCUACUGGAUCGGCGACAGCGUCAACACACCGCAGGCAGGCUACUUCGGCCUUUUCUCCUACUGCGUGGGUAACGUGCUGUCCUCCGAGCUCAUCUGCAAGGGCGGCCCCCUAGACUUCUCCUCCAUCCCCUCUAGAGCCUUCAAGACUGCCAUGUUCUUUGUGGCCUUGGGCAUGUUCCUCAUCAUUGGCUCCAUCAUCUGCUUCAGCCUGUUCUUCAUCUGCAACACGGCCACAGUCUAUAAGAUCUGUGCAUGGAUGCAGCUGGCUGCGGCCACAGGCCUAAUGAUUGGCUGCCUGGUCUACCCUGAUGGUUGGGACUCAAGUGAGGUGCGGCGCAUGUGUGGGGAGCAGACGGGCAAGUACACGCUGGGCCACUGCACCAUCCGCUGGGCCUUCAUGCUGGCCAUCCUCAGCAUUGGCGACGCCCUCAUCCUCUCCUUCCUGGCCUUCGUGUUGGGCUACCGGCAGGACAAGCUCCUCCCUGACGACUACAAGGCAGAUGGAACCGAGGAGGUGUGAAGCAGCUGAAGGGUCGGUCAUCUAUUUCCCAGACACAGGAAAACUAGGGAAUCAAAUUCUUCAGAGAUAAGAACUUGUUCUUCCAAGUUUCCUUGUUCCUGGCUACUAUAGGCCUGAAGCCUGAAGCCUUUUAUUAUAACACUAAAACUGGACAGUCUCCUGAGACAAGACCUCCUACUGUACUCUUUCUGGGGAAGCAGAACUGCAGUGACCCACUUCAAAGAUAUUCAGAGGCUGAGCGGUGCAGGGAGUGCUCAGUUGCUGGGGAUGGGAUCCAAGUCCAUUUCUUAGUUCCACACAGCAGCAAAUCGCUUCACCUUCUUGAAGCCUCUCCUCUGUAAAGCGAGAGGGCUAAAUGGGUCCAUCUCUAGGGGCCUUCCCUCCCAGGUCUGUGUCUGAUAGCAUACACACACACAUAUAUAUACACACACACACACACACACACACACACACACACACAUACAUACACACACACAUAUAUAUACACACACACACACACACACACACACACACUCUCUCUCUCUCUCAAACACACACAAAUGCCCAACCAGCUCUAAGAGGGCACUGAAGAGGUGGCUGGACAUGUGCUGGGUCAUUUUUAGGGUGAGGUGUAGGGGGUCUUUUGCUUCUCCCUUCUCAUAUUUUGUUUUCUUAUUGCUGCUCAGAGGGGGGUAAGGAAUGGAGGGGCCAUCAGAACUUGAAUCCUUUAACAUCCACCAGGAAGUUUUAUGAAGAGUGGGUGAUAGGAUCUAAAAUCUCUGCAGACUUUUUUCCUCCCGGGAGCCAAAUAUCACAUUUCCUUAUGGUGCCCACACUGACUCAACCAGAACUGGCUACCAGCUUCAGAAAUGUGUUACUUAUGUUCAAGUAAUUUGUUAUAGGAAUAGAUGACAUUUUUUUUUUUCAAAAACUUUGGAUUUGGCAUAUAGUCAUCUAUAGGGGGAUUGGUUCCAGGAUCCCCUGCAGAUGCCAAAAUACAUGGAUGCCCAAGUCCUCAGCUAAAAAUAGCGUAGUAUUUGCAUAUAACCUAUGCACAUCCUCCUGUAUACUUUAAAUCAUCUCUAGAUUACUUAUAAUACCUAAUACAAUGUAAAUGCUAUGUAAA